GCGCUCCGUUAACGGAAGAAACGAGAUGGAGGCUGAAGGCGAUCCGCAUAGAGAUGGAGUUUCACCGUGUUGCCCAGGCUGGUGUCGAACUCCUGAGCUCAGGUGAUUCGCCCGCCUCAGCUUCCCAAAGUGUUGGGAUUAUAGGCGUGAGCCACCGCACCUGGCACAUGCUGAAGUGCAAUGUUGUGAUCUCGGCUCACUGCAACCUCUGCCUCCCAGGUUCAAGCGAUUCUCCUGCUUUGGCCUCCUGAGUAGCUGGGAUUGCAGGUCAGUUGCUCUCCCUGGAAGGAAGAGUGUUCUCGGAUUUCACCUUAAAGGAGGAAGGCUGCCAGAACUGAACUAGCACUUCUGAAUAUCCUGAGGCGAGGUCCGGUGACUUCCUUGGGAAGCUCUGCCACGCCCCCACCCCACCCUACCCCACCCUACCCCACCACAGCAGGCGCUGGAGUCCUGGGACCACCAGGGUCUGAGGCCCAAAUCCUUCCUCACUAAGGGGAGGAGAGGGGUGUUCCGGCAGGGCAGGAUGGGAAGGCGUGCUUGGGCGGGAUUGUGACAUAAGAGUGCCCUGGUGACAUGGAGCAGAUCUGUGACAUAAAUAAAGGUGUCAUAAAGACAGGGCGGGGCUCACGCUUAGAAGGGGCACGAGCGUCUCGGAGCUGCCAGAAUGUCUUCUGCUCAGUGCCCGGCACUAGUGUGUGUCAUGUCCCGGCUGCGUUUCUGGGGCCCAUGGCCCCUCCUUAUGUGGCAACUAUUGUGGCUACUAGUUAAGGAGGCUCAGCCUCUGGAGUGGGUCAAGGACCCGCUCCAGCUCACCUCUAAUCCCCUGGGGCCGCCUGAGUCCUGGUCUUCCCACUCCUCCCAUUUCCCACGGGAAUCUCCCCAUGCGCCUACUCUCCCAGCAGACCCGUGGGACUUUGAUCACCUGGGGCCCUCUGCUUCCUCAGAGAUGCCAGCCCCACCCCAGGAAUCGACUGAAAAUUUGGUUCCAUUCCUGGACACCUGGGAUUCAGCUGGAGAGCAGCCCCUGGAGCCAGAGCAGUUCUUGGCUUCACAGCAGGAUUUAAAGGACAAGCUGAGUCCACAGGAAAGACUCCCUGUUUCGCCCAAGAAGCUGAAGAAAGAUCCAGCUCAGCGUUGGAGCCUUGCUGAGAUUAUUGGAAUUGCACGCCAAUUAUCCACACCUCAGAGUCAGAAACAGACUUUGCAGAAUGAAUAUUCCAGUACAGAUACACCGUAUCCCAGUAGCCUGCCUCCAGAACUCCGGGUGAAGUCAGAUGAGCCUCCAGGGCCCUCUGAGCAAGUUGGACCUUCUCAAUUCCAUCUAGAGCCCGAAACUCAAAAUCCAGAGACCCUUGAAGACAUCCAGUCCUCUUCACUCCAGCAAGAAGCCCCAGCACAGCUUCCACAGCUCCUUGAGGAAGAACCUUCUUCAAUGCAGCAGGAGGCCCCAGCUCUGCCUCCAGAGUCCUCUAUGGAGAGUCUAACUCUACCGAAUCAUGAGGUGUCAGUUCAACCUCCAGGUGAGGAUCAAGCUUAUUAUCACUUGCCCAACAUUACAGUUAAACCUGCAGAUGUGGAGGUUACCAUAACUUCAGAGCCUACCAAUGAGACAGAAUCUUCCCAAGCCCAGCAGGAGACCCCAAUUCAGUUUCCAGAGGAGGUGGAACCUUCUGCAACCCAACAGGAGGCCCCAAUUGAGCCUCCAGUUUCUCCUAUGGAGCAUGAACUUUCCAUCAGUGAGCAGCAGCAGCCAGUUCAGCCUUCUGAGUCUUCUAGGGAGGUCGAAUCUUCUCUGACCCAGCAGGAGACCCCAGGUCAGCCUCCAGAACAUCAUGAAGUCACAGUUUCACCUCCAGGUCACCAUCAAACUCAUCAUUUAGAUUCACCCAGUGUCUCUGUGAAGCCUCCAGACGUGCAGCUCACCAUAGCAGCAGAGCCUAGUGCAGAGGUGGGAACUUCUCUAGUCCACCAGGAGGCUACAGCUCGGCUCUCAGGGUCAGGUAAUGAUGUAGAACCUCCCGCCAUCCAGCACGGGGGCCCACCUCUGCUUCCAGAGUCAUCAGAAGAAGCUGGACCUUUAGCAGUUCAACAGGAGACUUCAUUUCAAUCUCCGGAACCUAUUAAUAAUGAGAACCCCUCUCCAACCCAGCAGGAGGCUGCAGCUGAGCAUCCACAGACCGCUGAGGAGGGUGAGUCUUCCCUAACCCAUCAGGAGGCCCCAGCUCAGACUCCAGAGUUCCCUAAUGUAGUUGUAGCUCAACCUCCAGAGCAUUCACACCUGACUCAAGCCACAGUUCAACCUUUGGAUCUGGGGUUUACCAUCACUCCAGAAUCCAUGACAGAGGUUGAACUUUCUCCAACCAUGAAGGAGACCCCAACUCAGCCUCCUAAGAAAGUUGUACCCCAACUUCGAGUAUAUCAAGGGGUAACAAAUCCAACACCAGGUCAGGAUCAAGCUCAGCAUCCAGUGUCACCCAGCGUUACAGUUCAACUUUUGGACCUGGGACUUACCAUCACUCCAGAACCCACUACGGAGGUUGGACAUUCUACAGCCCCGAAGAGGACUAUAGUUUCUCCAAAGCAUCCUGAGGUGACACUUCCACAUCCAGACCAGGUUCAGACUCAGCAUUCACACCUGACUCGAGCCACAGUUCAACCUUUGGACCUGGGGUUUACCAUCACUCCAAAAUCCAUGACAGAGGUUGAACCUUCUACAGCCCUGAUGACUACAGCUCCUCCUCCAGGACACCCUGAGGUGACACUUCCACCUUCAGACAAGGGUCAGGCUCAGCAUUCACACCUGACUCAAGCCACCGUUCAACCUCUGGACCUGGAGCUUACCAUAACUACAAAACCUACUACAGAGGUUAAACCAUCUCCAACCACAGAGGAGACCUCAACUCAGCCUCCAGACCUGGGACUUGCCAUCAUUCCAGAACCCACUACAGAGACUGGACAUUCUACAGCCCUGGAGAAGACUACAGCUCCUCAUCCAGACCGGGUUCAGAGUCUGCAUCGAAGCCUGACUGAAGUCACAGGUCCACCUACUGAACUAGAACCUGCUCAGGAUUCACUGGUGCAGUCUGAAAGUUACACCCAAAAUAAGGCUUUAACUGCACCAGAGGAACAGAAGGCCUCCACAAGCACCAACAUAUGUGAGCUCUGUACCUGCGGAGAUGAGAUGUUGUCAUGUAUUGAUCUCAACCCAGAGCAGAGGCUCCGCCAAGUGCCUGUGCCAGAGCCCAACACCCACAAUGGCACCUUCACCAUCUUAAAUUUCCAAGGAAACUAUAUUUCUUACAUUGAUGGAAAUGUAUGGAAAGCAUACAGUUGGACUGAGAAACUAAUUCUCAGAGAAAAUAACUUGACUGAAUUACACAAGGAUUCAUUUGAAGGCCUGCUAUCCCUCCAGUAUUUAGAUUUAUCCUGCAAUAAAAUACAGUCUAUUGAAAGACAUACAUUUGAACCACUACCAUUUUUGAAGUUUAUAAAUCUUAGUUGCAAUGUAAUUACAGAACUCAGCUUUGGAACAUUUCAGGCCUGGCACGGAAUGCAGUUUUUACAUAAGUUAAUUCUCAAUCCUCUGAUCUUACCUAGCCAUAUGGCCUGCUGCCUCUGCCAACUUAAAAACAGCAUUGAGGCUGUCUGCAAGACAGUCAAGCUGCAUUGCAACAGUGCAUGUCUGACAAACACCAUACAUUGUCCUGAAGAAGAAUCUGUAGGGAAUCCAGAAGGAGCAUUCAUGAAGGUGUUACAAGCCCGGAAGAAUUACACAAGCACUGAGCUGACUGUUGAGCCGGAGGAGCCCUCAGACAGCAGUGGCAUCAACUUGUCAGGCUUUGGGAGUGAGCAGCUAGACACCAAUGACGAGAGUGAUGUUAUCAGUGCACUAAGUUACUUGCCAUAUUUCUCAGCAGUAAACCUAGAUGUGGAAUCAAUGUUACUACCGUUCAUUAAACUGCCAACCACAGGAAACAGCCUGGCAAAGAUUCAAACUGUAGGCCAAAACCGGCAAAAAGUGAAUAGAGUCCUCAUGGGCCCAAUGAGCAUCCAGAAAAGGCACUUCAAAGAGGUGGGAAGGCAGAGCAUCAGGAGGGAACAGGGUGCCCAGGCAUCUGUGGAGAACGCUGCCGAAGAAAAAAGGCUCGGGAGUCCAGCCCCAAGGGAGCUGGAACAGCCUCACACACAGCAGGGGCCUGAGAAGUUAGCGGGAAACGCCAUCUACACCAAGCCUUCGUUCAGCCAAGAGCAUAAGGCAGCAGUCUCUGUGCUGACACCCUUCUCCAAGGGCGCGCCUUCUACCUCCAGCCCUGCAAAAGCCCUACCACAGGUGAGAGACAGAUUGAAAGAAACACACACUAUUUCCAUUUUAGAAAGUGCAAAGGCUAGAGUUACAAAUAUGAAGGCUUCUAAACCAAUUUCACAUUCCAGAAAAAAAUACCGCUUUCACAAAACUCGCUGCAUGACCCACAGAACACCCAAGGUCAAAAAGAGUCCAAAGUUCAGAAAGAAAAGUUAUCUGAGUAGACUGAUGCUCGCAAACAGGCCUCCGUUCUCUGCAGCGAAGAGCCUCAUAAAUUCCCCUUCACAAGGGGCUUUUUCAUCCUUAGGAGACCUGAGUCCUCAAGAAAACCCUUUUCUGGAAGUAUCUGCUCCUUCAGAACAUUUUAUAGAAACCACUAAUAUAAAAGACACAACUGCAAGAAAUGCCUUGGAAGAAAAUGUUUUUAUGGAAAACACUAACAUGCCAGAAGUCACCAUCUCUGAAAACACAAACUACAAUCAUCCUCCUGAGGCAGAUUCCGCUGGGACUGCAUUCAACUUAGGGCCAACUGUUAAACAAACUGAGACAAAAUGGGAAUACAACAACGUGGGCACUGACCUGUCCCCCGAGCCCAAAAGCUUCAAUUACCCAUUGCUCGCUCAGUUUGAAAUUCAGCUAACCCAGCAGCUACAGUCCCUUAUCCCCAACAACAAUGUGAGAAGGCUCAUUUCUCAUGUUAUCCGGACCUUGAAGAUGGACUGCUCUGGGGCCCAUGUGCAAGUGACCUGUGCCAAGCUCAUCUCCAGGACAGGCCACCUGAUGAAGCUUCUCAGUGGGCAGCAGGAAGUAAAGGCAUCUGAGAUAGAAUGGGAUACGGACCAAUGGAAGACUGAGAACUACAUUAAUGAGAGCACGGAAGCCCAGAGUGAACAGAAAGAGAAGUCGCUUGAGCUCACAAAAGAAGUUCCAGGAUACGGCUAUACUGACAAACUCAUCUUGGCAUUAAUUGUGACUGAAAUACUAAUGAUUUUGAUUAUACUUUUCUGCCUCAUUGUGAUGUGUUGUCACCGAAGGUCAUUACAAGAAGAUGAAGAAGGAUUCUCAAGGGACAGCGAAGCCCCAACAGAGAAGGGGGAGGAGAGUGAAGCCCUGCCAUAGGAGGAGAACCCAGCCCACCUCAGGCCUCCUGCAAAAACACAUAGCAUAAACAAUACCAUCAGAAAGAAAAGCAGGACUGAAGCCAGCGGCCCACACAUCCACAGAGGCAGCGGGCAGAGCAAGCACAGGGCCAUCGUUCCUGCCCUUGUUUCCCAGUCUAAUUAGUCACCCAGACCUGAAAACAUAUCCUCAGGGGGUGGAGAUUUUACAAUUACCAUUGUUUUUGGUGCCCUCUCCCUUGCUUCAUCAAGCAUCAGUCAUAUAAUACCACAGAUUUGAACUCCUGCCCACAGGGGACCUCCCAUCUCCUGGCCCCUAUCAUAGGAUCACUGGGCCUACCUGCACUGUGGGGCCAAGCCCUGUCUUUUUCCCAAGCCCUCAAGCACACGCAUGAGUGUUCAUCCCGACUUGGUAGGGGGCUUUUCACCCUUACAAGAUGGCAAAAGAUUCACAUUGCUUUUUUAAAAA